CUUUUUGCACACACACGAAUACAAAGAGCCAUACGACCUUCGGGUAUCCUUUUUCCAUUUUUUUUCCUCCUUAAUCUUGUGUGUGUUUUCAAAUUUUUUAAAAAUAGAGAUCUGUAGCAGUGUUGGGGUGAGGAAACUGUUGCUAAGGGGAAUUUGCUCUUUCCCCCAUUUCUUUUUCUGUCUCUCUUCCUCUUUCUUUUUCCUGGUCAAGGUUUUAAAUAUACCAAGAAGUUGAGAAGCAGGAUGGCCGUGUACAACCGUUUCCGGCCAAAUUUAUAGUUUUUUUUUCUUUUUUUUAAAUCACAUUUUAAGAACUGGUAGAUUUUUGUGGUUGAGGGACUUUAAAAAUUUAGCCGCUUGGGAAGUACAGAAUUUUUUAAGCGGGCUGAAGGGAUAAUGUAAAUUUCUGCCACAGGCAACAUCGAAGGAAGCAGAGAGAUUUGAGGCUCCCUCAUAAAGCCGUUUGCGUGCUUUUUACACACCCACCCCCCCAGAACCAAAACCAAGUGGCUGGGAUGUGGCACUUGUCCAAGGCCAAUAAGUUAAUAUUGGGAUAUUAUAAUGGAGACAUUCAUUUCCCUAGGGAAGGGGGAAAGACCUUAAUUACAGUGUGUCUUUCACACACAUUUUCAUUAGAACAUUUGUGUGUGUGUGUGUGUGUUUCUUGAAACAAAUUUGUAAAGUUAUAACUUGGGGUUAUUUGUGUAUAUGUACAAUAUGUGUGUAUAUGUGCCAUAUCAGAUUUUAUUUUCAAAAGUGAUAAAUAUAUCUGGUUUUAUGUGUGCAAAGUAUCCCCUAGGAUGUGAAUUUUUUUCCGUUGUCUUCCCAAAUGUGAUCAAAAUAUUUUGUGUGCAAAGCAGAGCUUAGAAGAAAUCCUAUGCUUAGCAUACUUAGGCACUUUCUAUGUGCAUUUACUAUAUUUUUCUGCUCCUAAAGGAUCAGAAUAAUGAAUAAUUAAAUAAUUGCCAAGGAGUAUAUAGUCCAUGUGGCAAAUGAGAGUAGGCAAUUUAUUGAAUCUGUGGUUCAAAGCCUUCAGUGACUGUUUUGCCUAAGUGGUUUUGCUUUUUAUUGUCUCACGUUCUUAAGUGUACAGCUGUGUAUAUUUUGGCCUUUAUGUGUGGUUUGGUUGGUGUGUUCAGAAGGGAAGUUCUUUCUUGGCUUUUUGACAAAAUGGUCGUUUAUUGGUUGGAAUAUUCGAAAAGCUCCACAGCUGGCAAAGUAUCAGGAAAAAAAUCCAGUCAAGUGUAAUUCUCAAAAACUGUUCAUGGUGAUGGUGAUGGGGAGCCAAGAGGAUGCAAAGGCAAAUAAUAGAAGGGAUAAGAAAUGCCUUUUGGUUAUCAUGUUGCAUUUUUAGAAUGGAAAGCUUCUCAUUUCUAAGAGUCACAGAAAAAAGUAUAUGAAUUAGAGAAAAACAGGCUCGCAGAGCAGAACCUCCUGUUAUAGGAGCCCUAUUUUCACUUCAUUCUGUUACAGAAUCACUAUCUCCUCAUUAGAAGUUGUAUGGAAAAUAUCUGUAUCCAAAUUUGUAUUCGCAGAUUGGAGUGAAAGCAUAGGAGGUAUAUGAGGUGCUGAGGGAGAAACUGGAAUGUCACAAAUGCAGUGACAACCAGGAGACAAAAAAAAAAAUCUACUGUAGAAUUUAAAUUUCAUUACAACAAAACUUCUGUAUAAUAAUGCAUUUCUAUUACACAGCUAGCAUCCUACUCUAUUUCAAGCAGUAUUUGACUCCUAAAUACUGACUGCAAUAAAGUUACUUGUACAAAUUUAUAACAAAAGUGGCCCUGUUUGGGCUUUCUGGGUUUCUUACUUGUGCUGAGUGUAUUUUUAUUCUCUAACAAUUCAAGUCAGACCAGUGCUUAAUAAAUACUGGCUCGACUGUGGAUUAUUCCACAAUUUCAGACCUGCAUUUCUUUGAAAUCUAGUCACAUUUUAGUGAUCUUUGUGAUCACAACAGUGAUGGGAGUUUUUUUUUUUUUUUUUUUUUUUUUUGAAACGGAGUUUCGCUCUUGUUGCCCAGGCUGCAGUGGCAAUGGUGCGAUCUUGGCUCACUGCAACCUUCGCCUCCUGGGUUCAAGCGAUUCUCCUGUCUCGGCCUCCCGAGUAGCUGGGAUUACAGGCAUGUGCCACCAUGCCGGGCUGAUUUUUGUAUUUUUAGUAGAGACGGGGUUUCACCAUGUUGGUCAGGCUGGUCUCCAACUCCUGACUUUAGGUGAUCCGCCCGCCUCUGCCUCUCAAAGUGCUGGGAUUACAGGCGUGAGCCACCGCGCCCGGCCAGUUACGGGAAUUUUUAAUGGAGUUUUACCCUUUUUAGCUCUUUUCCACAUCACUACAGGUCAUCACAUAUACUUUUUACCUUACUUUUUAGCGUCUCAAAAAAUAGGGAGAGCUCUCCCUGAACAGUGCAGAGCCCGUAUCCCUGAUUUCCUAGGCUAUUUGAUUUCUACAUCCAGGAACGUAGGGUCAUAUCCACUGUUCUUGCUUUUUCUUCCUAAGAAAGGAGAGAAUUCCUCGCACAUAUAUAUCGUUGGCUUGGCCUUCCAAAGCAAAGCAAAACUAAACUCUGUUGAUUUUGCCUGGGAAUCCUCGGGGCCCCUAGUAUUGGAAACUUCUUUGAACUGUGAGGAGCUGCUAAUUUGCAGGUGACAUGUGAAAGAAAUGUAACCGAGGCCAGCAGUAACUAAAAGUCGGCCACCACCCAACGUGUGACGCCGAUUUGUGGCCACUGUGCUUAUAAUCGUGUACACACAGGUUUGUGAGCAGCAGAGAACAAAAGCAAGUAAACAAAAACAAGCUAAAGAUGGCGUCUGACGGCCUUGAAAAAGCCUCACAGUCUUGUCCCUCCCUGAGGAGGCCCCUCCCCUACCUGACUUUUUGAGUGACUGUUGUUUGCAGCCAAUAGUGUCCGUGACCCUGCUCCCCAGCCAUCGUCUAACCGCCAAUCACCGGGAGCCAGAAGGCAAACGGGGCGGUGUCUCCCCGCGUGCGCGCGGUAGCCGGGUACACGGGCAGGCGCCGCGGAUAGUUCUGUCUCCCGCGCGCCCGCCUCCGCCUCUGCCUAGCUGAGUCAGCCCGUGCGGUAGCGCCAGGCACACGCGGUAGAACAUCUGUAGGGCUGCAAAGCUGCACCUCCGCGUCAGUUCUCACGGCGAGCGCCGCCUUCAGCCCAAGUUCUCAAAGCUCUCGGGGCUACGUAGUCUACCCUCCCCGGUGACCCGGCGAGAUCCCUAGCCGCUCCUCCGGCCGCUCUGCUCUCCGCAUCCCUCGCGGGAAUGACCCCCUUUACCCGGGACUCCCAGAGCGCACUGUAUGGUAGGGCACAGUGGCGAGUCACCCUGUCCCCUGAGGCCUCUUGAGCAGUCGCCGAUCUCUGCUUCCCGCGUCGCUGCGAUCGCCUUUCCCGUAGCUGAAUCACACUGACCCAUCGGAAACGGUUCUGCCCUCCCUGGGGUCCACCUUGUCAUCCUUGACUAAUAUUUAAUCAACUAACAUUUACCAAGUUCUCGCUGGCACGAGUUCUAGGAGCUACUUUUUCAUUUUUCAGUUUCUCCAUAAAUGCAGUGGGUCCUUUAGGCAAACCUGAAAUCGGAAAUAUUAAUCUUACCAAUGUAAUCUUAGCAAAUGUAAAUAAAAAGGACUGUGCUAUACUGGGCUAAAAAUUCUCAUCCUGCUAUAGAAAUAUACGUGGAAUUUUCAGAUUACGUGGAAUCCUUUAAAGACCGCAUUCGGCCUUCUGGGUCUACAGCUCUCUUUUUUACCCCUAAAAAUAAGGUCUUGGAUUUUUUGCAGACCAUUAGUCGAGUCACUCUUUUAAAAUGUGGGAAAAUAGUAUUUUGUGGUAUUUACUUAGCUGCUCUUGUGUGAUAAGGAGCUCAUUUCUGAUAAAAAUAGGUUUUGAGAGAACCUUUUGACAGGUGAGCCAUUUUGCACCUUGAAGUGGAGGAGUAGGACUGACCAACACAGCAGGAGCUUUAAGUGGCCGUUUUCCUUAUUUAUUUCUUAAAAUGAAGAUUAUGAUAUGAAUUGCCAUGCUUUCAGUAAUCACAUUUAAGGAAGUCUAUUGCUAGCAUGACCCUGAAUGAGUCAAGCACCCAUUAUAAAAACAUAUAUCAUCUGAGUGAUACCAUAUCAUACACAUCUAUUAAAUAGUGAGAAAACUUUUAUUUUUCAUAGUUUGGAGGUGAACUCAGUCAUGCAGAAAAUUCAAACUCAGAAUGGGGAGAAAGCAAGCAAGGGAACUGCCAAGAGUAUGAUAUAUUUAGUCCUAACAAAAAUGUGACUUGGGAGGAAAGGGAUAGUUAAAAUUAUGGACAGUCUUACCCUGAACUGUCUGUCUAAAGGAGAUGAAUUGUCUUUCUUUUUUAUCUAAAUAUUUAUGAAAAAUACCAAAAGUACUGGAAAGUACAUUUUUAAGGCUCGUUUCACAUUUAUUUAAAUUAGACCAAUACUGAAAUGAACCCCAAAUGCUUAUAUUUUUUGCAAACCUAAGUGUGACAUCUACUGUCAUGUUGUGUUGGCAACGCAUCCCAAGAUUGAAGAUCUUUUUCUCUUUUUUAGACCUAGUCAGUUGUUUUCAGGACUUUCUACUUAAACAUGUUGCCAUCAUUUGAAAUUUAAAAUGUUAAAUAAAUACACUUCUUCUCUAAUAUACUGGUGUCUCCUCUUUUUAUUUAUUUAUUUUUUAGAGACUGGGUCUUGCUAUGCUGCCGAGGUUGGUCUCAAACUCCUGGGCUCAAGCGAUCCUCCUCCUCCCAAAGUGCUGGGAUUACAGGCAUGAGCCACCAUGCCCAGCCAUGGUAUUUCCUCUCAACUGCCUCAUUUCUGUCAUUCUGGUGGUGGUGGUGGUACCAUCCUGUUACUCUUAGGCUUAUAACCUUGCAGUUGUCUUUAACCAAUUAUCUCUAUACCCCAUCUCUAUAACUCUGUCAAUUCUCCUUAUCUUACUAUAUAAGCGCCUUUGCUCUGACCUCUGACAUGUACCCUGUUAAGUCCUGUAAUUUUUUUUUUUUCCUCUAGAAUGUCUUACUACCCUAUCAGUUAAUCCUAUACAUUGCUCAAGGCUCAACUGGAAGCUUUUCUUCUUUUCAGGUUUAGCUGUGCCUCCCAGUGACUAUAAUGACAAGGAAGCUGUAAAUGUAUUUGAGUUAAGCUUUUGCGAGAAGCAAAGUGACAGCAUAGCUGUUCAAACAUUCCUGUUGAAUUUUGGAUCCACCCUUAAGGAGCUUGAGAAAUGAAGAUAAGGGGCCCCACGGGUGAUUUCUCUGGGCUCCUGGCUGGAAGAUUCAGGACAGCUAGUUUCCAUUACAGAGGCUCAUGGCCCAGGUACACGACUAUGUGGGAAAGGGGGCUGUGCAGCCCUGGGUUACCCCAGCUCAAUUCCCUGAUCUUUUCAUUUCAUUUCCCUGCCCUCAUCCCCAAAGCAUUAAUGAUAUAAUAUAACAGUGAGAAGUUGGUGACAUGCUGAGGGCUGCAGUGAUGGAUGUAUUCCUUAUUUAGGAGUGUUACUCUGAAUGCAUUUGUAUGAAAAUUACAGAGAGGGUAGAAUCAUGAUUGUCAUGAUUGUUAAUGUCAACAAAAAGUGGUAUCAGUUAAAAAAAAAUACAACACUACAUUGAAAGUAGCAAUAACUGGAUUCUGCUGUUAUUCCUCUGACCUUGAAAAAGACAUAUAACUUCUCCACAUGUCUCUUCUCUGGACCUGGAGUAAUAUGUUUCCUAGUGCUGUUGAGUAGAUGAGGUAACUUAUGUGAAGUGUUCUGAACACCUUAAGGAACAAUGUCAAAGCAAUGAAAUGCAGUACCAUUAUUACAGUAAAGAUGGUGAGGAGGAGGAGGAGACAGAUCUACAUUUUCUUCCUUAAUCUUCUAAUCUUUCCAGAUGCCGGAAGGUCCUUCUGAAUCCCUUCCCUGUUCCUUAGGUUGCACUAGUCGGGGGUUCCAUGCUGGGGGGCAGAAGGAAUGCUCUCUACCGUCUGAAACCGUUCAUCAGGAAGGCCUUGAUUUGUGAUGUGCUAGGAGAGCACAGGAUCUGCAAAUAGAAGGCACCUGUCUCCCUUCUGCAGGCCGAGGAGAGGCCGCCAUGGACUGUGUGCUUCUUCAUGGCUUGUUUACUCUUCUUUCACAGACCCUACAGCUUGGGGCCUGGGCUCCUCUGACCAUCCUCAUUGAGAAAGGAAAGUGAGUCCAGAGAAGUUGAUGCUUCCUACCUGUUGGAGCGGCCCAGCAGUGAGGAAGUGGGUGACCUGAGGCAAGGGAAAGUGUCCAUCCCUGAUGAAGAUGGGGAAAGCCGGGCACAUAGUUCCCCACCUGAGGAGCCUGGGCCUCUCAAGGAAAGUCCCGGGGAAGCCUUUAAGGCUCUGUCUGCCGUGGAAGAGGAGUGUGACAGCGUGGGCAGCGGCGUGCAGGUGGUGAUUGAGGAGCUGCGGCAGCUGGGAGCAGCCUCAGUGGGGCCUGGGCCUUUGGGCUUCCCAGCAACUCAGAGGGACAUGCGGCUCCCAGGGUGCACGCUGGCUGCCAGCGAGGCGGCCCCCCUGCUCAAUCCUCUGGUGGAUGAUUACGUGGCCUCUGAGGGUGCAGUACAGCGAGUUCUGGUCCCUGCUUAUGCCAAGCAACUCUCACCAGCCACACAACUGGCAAUCCAGCGGGCAACCCCAGAGACAGGACCAGAAAAUGGAACCAAGCUGCCACCACCCCGCCCUGAGGACAUGCUCAAUGCCGCUGCUGCGCUGGACAGUGCCUUGGAAGAGUCAGGCCCUGGGAGCACUGGGGAGCUGAGACACUCUCUAGGGCUGACCGUUUCCCCAUGCAGGACCAGAGGAAGUGGGCAGAAGAACUCCAGGCGCAAGCGGGAUCUUGUACUCUCUAAACUGGUCCACAAUGUGCAUAACCACAUCACCAAUGACAAGAGAUUCAAUGGGUCUGAAAGCAUCAAGUCCUCUUGGAAUAUUUCAGUAGUGAAGUUUCUUCUGGAAAAGCUCAAGCAAGAGCUGGUGACCAGUCCCCACAAUUACACUGAUAAGGAGCUAAAAGGAGCCUGUGUGGCCUACUUCCUUACUAAGAGGCGUGAGUACCGCAACUCCCUGAACCCCUUUAAAGGCCUGAAGGAAAAAGAGGAGAAGAAACUUCGAAGUCGCCGAUAUCGGCUUUUUGCCAACCGAUCCAGUAUCAUGAGGCAUUUUGGACCUGAGGACCAACGUCUGUGGAAUGAUGUGACAGAGGAACUGAUGUCAGAUGAAGAGGACAGUCUUAACGAGCCAGGUGUGUGGGUGGCCCGCCCUCCCCGUUUCCGGGCCCAGCGCCUCACAGAGCUCUGCUACCACCUGGAUGCUAACUCUAAGCAUGGCACCAAAGCCAACCGUGUGUAUGGGCCUCCCUCAGACAGACUGCCUUCUGCUGAAGCCCAGCUCCUUCCACCAGAACUUUACAAUCCUAAUUUCCAAGAAGAGGAAGAUGAGGGAGGGGAUGAGAAUGCACCUGGCUCCCCAUCUUUUGACCAACCCCACAAAACCUGCUGUCCUGACUUGAACUCAUUCAUUGAAAUCAAGGUGGAAAAGGAUGAAUAAAAUCUACAGCCAAGAAUAACUCUGGCUUCCGCCAUGCCCCAUGUCUCAGAAAUAGGUGGCCAUGGGGCUUCACAAAAUAAUGAGAUGCUCUGUGCAGUCUGAGAAAGCAAAUUUGCCUCUUUUCUUAACACAGUCUCUACUGGGGAAGCAGAACACUGGUGGGAUAAAAACUUAUCUAGAAGGGGAGAAACUCCCUCCACUGUGAACAGUAAGCCAGAAUAUGCUUAUUCCUCAGCAUAAACAGUAUCUCGGAGAAGCCUGGGAUGAGAAAAUGAGGAGGAUGGGUCCAAGAAACAUGAGGCCUUCUUGACAUAUGCCCUGUCUCUGAGUUGUUUCUGCCCCUGCCCAGUUCCACCCAAAGCUCUGAGGAAGCAGCCCAGGUUGUACCUUUUGCUUCCCUGUGACUACUUGUCUUGCUCUGCAGUGGAAACCGAACAUGACCAGUGCAGGUUAAUACCGCCACCUGGUGGGCAGUUUCAGUCAUGAGCUUGAGUCUUCUGACCAAGGGAACACAAGUUCUAUCACUAUUGGGGAAUUGGGUUCCUGAUAUAAUAGCUAUUGUUUAUUGAAUUACAUGAGGAAAAUUUUACUAUUCCUAUCUUACAGAUGAGGAAAUUAAGGCUUAAAGAGUUCCCGUGUCUCACCGGCAGCCUCUCUCUCACUAUGUGACCAAGCAAAAUACACAGCUUUGUAGCUGUUUCUUGGUCCUGUCAGCCAAGCUGUAUUUUGAGGAAGGGGUGUGCAUUUUGGAUGGAUUGAAAAGCAAAAAUGGCUUUACAUUUAUUCAGUCUUAUAACAAACAUUGAUCGCUUUACUAGGUGUCAGGUACUGUGCUAUGGAUACAUUGUUGAUAAGGUUGGAUGCUGUUCAGAGAUUUUUUUAGUUUAGUCAGGAAGCCAGGCAGUGGAGUAGGCAAUGAAAUGAACUGUGAUAAGGGUGACCAUGGUGGAGUGUAGUGCACUAUGGCAAUAUACAGCAGGGGUAGCUAACCUACUCUUGCAGUCUGGAAAGGCUUCUUCUGAGAGGGUGUAAUGUCUAAACUGGGGAAGAGUUAACCAGAAGGAAAGGGGAGGCUAAGAGAGUGUUCCAAACAGGGAACUGCAGGUACAAAAGUCCAGGGGCAAGAGAGAGUACAGACAAGGUCCAGUUCUACUGCAGACUUUUGGGGAAGGGAUAAUGCUAGAGGAGAGGCUGGAGAGUGAGACAGACCUCAUAAUACAGAGUACAGACUUCAACCCAAGGGCAGUGAGAAAUCAUUGAAAGUUUGUUUUAGCAGGGAAAUAAAACGACAGGUUUUGCCUACAGGCAGUCCCCAACUCAA